GCCCCCGCCUGCCCCGCCCGGCGCCGCACCACGUGGGCCAGGCGCCCCACGCCUGGAGCUCCCCUCUCUGGAGCCCCGGGAAAGGAAGCGGGGCAGGGAGGCCGGGUGGGAGCAGGGGGGUCUCCGGCGCUUCCUCUCCUCUGCGGGCGCCGCGCGGCUCCUGAGAGUCCGCCCCCCGUCCUGACGCUCAGCUAGGAAGCGGGUCCUCGGGCCCCUCCCCCGACACACACACACACACACACACACACACACACACACACACACACUCUCUCUCUCUCUCUCUCUCUCUCUCUCUCUCUCUCUCUCUCUCACACACACACACACACACACAGCCCGUCUCGCGCCUGAGGUCUCGCCCGCAGGCCGGUGGCGCGGGGUCAGCUGCUGCCUGCGGUCCAGGACAGGGUCGGUUCCGCCGCGCAGCGCCCAGGCCCAGCUCGUCCAGAGUCUGCGGACAGCGCACGUCCAGUCGUGGCAUUCCUGGUGGCUUUCCAUCAGAACAAGCAGCUCAUCGGUGACAGGGGGCUGCUUCCCUGCAGAGUGUUCCUGAAGAACUUCCAGCAGUACUUCCAGGACAGGACGAGCUGGGAAGUCUUCAGCUACAUGCCCACCAUCCUCUGGCUGAUGGACUGGUCAGACAUGAACUCCAACCUGGACUUGCUGGCUCUUCUCGGACUGGGCAUCUCGUCUUUCGUACUGAUCACGGGCUGCGCCAACAUGCUUCUCAUGGCUGCCCUGUGGGGCCUCUACAUGUCCCUGGUUAAUGUGGGCCAUGUCUGGUACUCUUUCGCCUCUGCCAUCAGCCUUCCCAGUAUGCACGGAGGGCAGUGAUGGGCGCUUGUGAUCUGAUCCGUGCCUCCUCCCUGGAUGUGGGAGCUCCUGGGCUUCCAGGCCCCGGGCACCUAGAGACGGAUGGUCGCACGCAUGAUUGUCGGCAUCUCACAGGAUGGGAGUCCCAGCUUCUGGAGACGGGGUUCCUGGGGAUCUUCCUGUGCCCUCUGUGGACGCUGUCAAGGCUGCCCCAGCAUACCCCCACAUCCCGGAUUGUCCUGUGGGGCUUCCGGUGGCUGAUCUUCAGGAUCAUGCUUGGAGCAGGCCUGAUCAAGAUCCGGGGGGACCGGUGCUGGCGAGACCUCACCUGCAUGGACUUCCACUAUGAGACCCAGCCGAUGCCCAAUCCUGUGGCGUACUACCUGCACCACUCACCCUGGUGGUUCCAUCGCUUCGAGACGCUCAGCAACCACUUCAUCGAGCUCCUGGUGCCCUUCUUCCUCUUCCUCGGCCGGCGGGCGUGCAUCAUCCACGGGGUGCUGCAGAUCCUGUUCCAGGCCGUCCUCAUCGUCAGCGGGAACCUCAGCUUCCUGAACUGGCUGACUAUGGUGCCCAGCCUGGCCUGCUUUGAUGACGCCACCCUGGGAUUCUUGUUCCCCUCUGGGCCAGGCAGCCUGAAGGACCGAGUUCUGCAGAUGCAGAGGGACAUCCGAGGGGCCCGGCCCGAGCCCAGAUUCGGCUCCGUGGUGCGGCGUGCAGCCAACGUCUCGCUGGGCGUCCUGCUGGCCUGGCUCAGCGUGCCCGUGGUCCUCAACUUGCUGAGCUCCAGGCAGGUCAUGAACACCCACUUCAACUCUCUUCACAUCGUCAACACUUACGGGGCCUUCGGAAGCAUCACCAAGGAGCGGGCGGAGGUGAUCCUGCAGGGCACAGCCAGCUCCAACGCCAGCGCCCCCGAUGCCAUGUGGGAGGACUACGAGUUCAAGUGCAAGCCAGGUGACCCCAGCAGACGGCCCUGCCUCAUCUCCCCGUACCACUACCGCCUGGACUGGCUGAUGUGGUUCGCGGCCUUCCAGACCUACGAGCACAACGACUGGAUCAUCCACCUGGCUGGCAAGCUCCUGGCCAGCGACGCCGAGGCCUUGUCCCUGCUGGCACACAACCCCUUCGCGGGCAGGCCCCCGCCCAGGUGGGUCCGAGGAGAGCACUACAGGUACAAGUUCAGCCGUCCUGGGGGCAGGCACGCCGCCGAGGGCAAGUGGUGGGUGCGGAAGAGGAUCGGAGCCUACUUCCCUCCGCUCAGCCUGGAGGAGCUGAGGCCCUACUUCAGGGACCGUGGGUGGCCUCUGCCCGGGCCCCUCUAGACGUGCACCAGAAAUAAAGGCGAAGACCCAGCCCCUCGGCGGCUCAGCAACGUUUGCCCUUCCCUGCGCCCAGCCCAAGCUGGGCAUCGCCAAGAGAGACGUGGAGAGGAGAGCGGUGGGACCCAGCCCCCAGCACGGGGGUCCAGGGUGGGGUCUGUUGUCACAUACUGUGGCGGCUCCCAGGCCCUGCCCACCUGGGGCCCCACAUCCAGGCCAACCCUUGUCCCAGGCGCCAGGGGCUCUGAUCUCCCAUCCAUCCCACCCUCCUCCCAGAGGCCCAGCCUGGGGCUGUGCCGCCCACAGGAGUUGAGACAAUGGCCAUCCUGACACCUUCCUCCACUACAGCCCUGACCAUAGACCCAGCCAGGUAGCUCUUGGGGUCUCUAGCGUCCCAGGGCCUGGUUUCUGUUCCCUCUUCAAUGGUGUGUUCCCAGCCAGGUCCUGACCCUCAGAGCCAAGUCCCUGUCACGUCUGGGGCAGCCAAACCCUCGCCCCACAGGGACCUGGACACGCCCGGCCAGGAUGUGGGGUUGGAUGGGCCAUUUUCUGUCCUAUCCCUCAUCUCCACCCCCGCCACAGCCUACACGCAUCCCACACAUGCAGGCACACACAGCCUGUGCACACAUGUGUUCUUGGCCCGGUUUCAUCCCCCCAUGACUGGUGUCUGUGAGGUGCAGAUGGACACAGCGCACACCCAGACCCUCCACCAGGCUGUGACCUCGCUGCCUCUGAGGCCUUGACAAGGCCCCUCAAUCGGAGGACAGCCGGCCGUGCACACUUUCAUCAUCGUCGGACAAACAGCGUCUACUGCACAUUUUUCUUAUUCCUAUUCUUGAGCCAUAGCUAUGGCAUAUUCUUCUACUAUUCCUAUUAUACCACUUACCAGCUUACUCGAAAA